AUGUGCUCCCCGGAAAGGUCGAGAAUCUCCGUCUCCCUGCGGUCUCCGGCCGCUCAGCCCGCUUACUGAGCUCGGGAGACGCCGGCGCCUAAUCCUGGGCUCGGAAUGUGGGGGCCAGCCAGGCUGGGCCGCCAGCGCCCUUCGGAGCUGGGUGGGGCCGCUCAGUCCGGUCGCCCGCGGGAGCAAAGCGGGACCGCCUCCCCGCCCGGCUCCUCCAGCCUGACGGCCGCGUGGGACUGCGCUCCAGUGGGAGGGCGCCGGGGAGAUGCUCUGUCACCUGUCGGUUAAGGCGCUGCUGCUUAACCUUUCGCUGGUCCACCCGCAACGGCCCUUCCGUUUUCUUUGUCACUCGUAAAGUCUCAUAUAAUGGCAGCAAAGGCUGUAGCAAAUACAAUGAGAACAUCACUUGGACCAAAUGGGCUUGAUAAGAUGAUGGUGGAUAAGGAUGGAGAUGUGACUGUAACUAAUGAUGGGGCCACCAUCUUAAGCAUGAUGGAUGUUGAUCAUCAGAUUGCCAAGCUGAUGGUGGAACUGUCCAAGUCUCAGGAUGAUGAAAUUGGAGAUGGAACCACAGGAGUGGUUGUCCUGGCUGGUGCCUUGUUAGAAGAAGCGGAGCAAUUGCUAGACCGAGGCAUUCACCCAAUCAGAAUAGCCGAUGGCUAUGAGCAGGCUGCUCGUGUUGCUAUUGAACACCUGGACAAGAUCAGCGAUAGCGUCCUUGUUGACAUAAAGGACACCGAACCCCUGAUUCAGACAGCAAAAACCACGCUGGGCUCCAAAGUGGUCAACAGUUGUCACCGACAGAUGGCUGAGAUUGCUGUGAAUGCCGUCCUCACUGUAGCAGAUAUGGAGCGGAGAGACGUUGACUUUGAGCUUAUCAAAGUAGAAGGCAAAGUGGGCGGCAGGCUGGAGGACACUAAACUGAUUAAGGGCGUGAUUGUGGACAAGGAUUUCAGUCACCCACAGAUGCCAAAAAAAGUGGAAGAUGCGAAGAUUGCAAUUCUCACAUGUCCAUUUGAACCACCCAAACCAAAAACAAAGCAUAAGCUGGAUGUGACCUCUGUCGAAGAUUAUAAAGCCCUUCAGAAAUACGAAAAGGAGAAAUUUGAAGAGAUGAUUCAACAAAUUAAAGAGACUGGUGCUAACCUAGCAAUUUGUCAGUGGGGCUUUGAUGAUGAAGCAAAUCACUUACUUCUUCAGAACAACUUGCCUGCGGUUCGCUGGGUAGGAGGACCUGAAAUUGAGCUGAUUGCCAUCGCAACAGGAGGGCGGAUCGUCCCCAGGUUCUCAGAGCUCACAGCCGAGAAGCUGGGCUUUGCUGGUCUUGUACAGGAGAUCUCAUUUGGGACAACUAAGGAUAAAAUGCUGGUCAUCGAGCAGUGUAAGAACUCCAGAGCUGUAACCAUUUUUAUUAGAGGAGGAAAUAAGAUGAUCAUUGAGGAGGCGAAACGAUCCCUUCACGAUGCUUUGUGUGUCAUCCGGAACCUCAUCCGCGAUAAUCGUGUGGUGUAUGGAGGAGGGGCUGCUGAGAUAUCCUGUGCCCUGGCAGUUAGCCAAGAGGCGGAUAAGUGCCCCACCUUAGAACAGUAUGCCAUGAGAGCGUUUGCCGACGCACUGGAGGUCAUCCCCAUGGCCCUCUCUGAAAACAGUGGCAUGAAUCCCAUCCAGACUAUGACCGAAGUCCGAGCCAGACAGGUGAAGGAGAUGAACCCUGCUCUUGGCAUCGACUGUUUGCACAAGGGGACAAAUGAUAUGAAGCAACAGCAUGUCAUAGAAACCUUGAUUGGCAAAAAGCAACAGAUAUCUCUUGCAACACAAAUGGUUAGAAUGAUUUUGAAGAUUGAUGACAUUCGUAAGCCUGGAGAAUCUGAAGAAUGAAGACAUUGAGAAAACUAUGUAGCAAGAUCCACUUCUGUGAUUAAGUAAAUGGAUGUCUCGUGAUGCAUCUACAGUUAUUUAUUGUUACAUCCUUUUCCAGACACUGUAGAUGCUAUAAUAAAAAUAGCUGUUUGGUAACCAUAGUUUCACUUGUUCAAAGCUGUGUAAUCGUGGGGGUACCAUCUCAACUGCUUUUGUAUUCAUUGUAUUAAAAGAAUCUGUUUAAACAACCUUUAUCUUCUCUUCGGGUUUAAGAAACGUUUAUUGUAACAGUAAUUAAAUGCUGCCUUAAUUGAAGGGGUUUGGGUGGAUUUUUUUUUCUCAAAAUAAGCUGUAGGGACUAUUUUAACAGCUUAAACAGGAGCUCUCAAGAUGCACUUUCAUAUUGAGAGGAAUAUGGGCUUGAUCCUCUUCCUAUCUAAAUGGGUGGGCCAUUUGAUUGUAGAGGGUCCACCACAGAAUUAUGGGAUGCCUUAAGUGCUGUUACUAGGUUGCUCACAGCCUAACCUGGCGUGUUGUUUAGGGCUGAUGGAGACCCAUGUGAGCCUUUGCUUUCCUCUGGCCCCGGCCCCACCCUGAACACAGCUCAUACACAGAAUCAGGACCAGCAUGUGCAGAGCUGGCCACCAGCACAGGCUUAGGGCAGUUCAGAACCCACUUGUUUCCCUAUCAGAGGGACACAGUGAAGUGGAGGUUAAAGUAAAUUACAGGAAAUAAGGGAGAAAUCUUGCAGUUACCAUGUUCAGAUAGAGUGACUGAAAUUAAUUGUACUUACUAAAGUAUUAACUAGCUAACAGUGAUGGGCCAAGACGCUCCGAGAACUCUACCGGGAUUGUCUGUUCUGACAACCCAGUGAGGCAGAUACACUUUCUUACUGCUCACAUCUUACAGGUGAGUACUCAUAAUUGGCCAGCAUCUCACCACCAGCAAGUAGUAGGGCCAGGUCAAUCCCAGGCAGUCUGACCCCAGAGUGGCCCAGCUCAUCCCCUACUCUGUUAUUUGCUUGUUAAUGAUUCUCUAGAUUUUCUAAAAUAAUGUUUCUUAGCAUUGUGAUGAUAAAGCUCAUGAUGAACUUUAUCACUAGUUAUGCCACCUUAACUAGUCAGAUUUCCUAGAAUUAGGAAAUGGUGACUCUUGUCUAAAUUUGGUUAAGUGAUGAAUUUGGGUUACCGUCUCAUGUGAACCUGGAGAUUCACCAGUCUUAACUUUUGGGUCAUUGUGUUUUCUCUACAUUCAUGCAUUGGAUGUUUUGCUAAAUAACUCCUGUGGAUUUAGGAAUGUGUGCUAAUAGCAAUCUUCCUAAUUUUCAUGUUUAUAUGGAACUAUGCAGUUGAGUAUUGAAAGCUUUAAACUGAGUUUAUUUACAAGGACUGAGUCUAGCCUACAGAGAACAUACAGCAGCCUUCUUUGGACCACAGUCUUAUCCGAGGGGUCUGUGGUUGUAUCAGAAGAGCCACUAAACCAAUCCCCCUUUCCAAAAUUGAACCUCACAGACGUUCCUGUUUUUUGUGAUUGAGAAACUGGUCAAUGAACAGGAAGACUUAGAGAUGUUUCACAAGCCUUUGAUUUUUGUUUCAUUUAUUUGUAAUAAACCUCUUCCACGUGA